GUAACAACUCUCAGAGGAGCAUUGCCCGUCAGACAGCAACUCAGAGAAUAACCAGAGAACAACCAGGUAUUUCAAUGAUUUCCAUGCCAUGUCUAUGGGAAAUAGGGUUUCAUGUUUUCUCUUCCCUCAUGCUGGUAUUAAUAGAUUGAAAAUUUGGAUGUGGGGUGUUUGUAGAGGGCGAGUAAAAUUUAAGUGGUGUUUUCUUGUUUAGUUGUUGAAUUGAAAAUAUUUUAUUUCAAGAUUUGAAUUAAAUUUAUAAGGUUUAAUUUUGAAUCUCAGAAGCCAACAAAUACCUUUGUAGCAUUAACCAAAACAAAAUGUACAUUCAGAUUGUGAUGCCAAUUUUAUUGAACAGAUUAGAUUAUAUAUGUUCUCUACUAGCUACUGUUUUGACACUAAAUUUGAUGGAAACAACUAGAUACAUUAAAAUAUUUUCAUUUAAGCAAUUGAAUGUAAUCUCUACAUUGUAUAUAAAUAAUAGGAAAAGAAGACUUCAUUUGCACCUUAAAUGAAAAAGCAGGAACUGCAAAAAUUAAGUAGCAAUUUGGGCUGGGUCAAUCUAGUACAACAAUAUGUUUAUUGAGUUUAGUUCAAUAAUGGGUCAAUUUAGUGAAAGAGAAUAAUCAGCCAAAGUAGUUGCAGGGUUGACUGAAGUAUGGUUCAGUAAAUAACUUAAUAUCCCAUAAAAAGAUACUUAUUCAUUAUGAAAGCCAUCAACUAGGAGAAAUUGCUUUUAAUUCUGUUGGGGGAGAUGUAGCAGUAUUUGAUGAGAUAUUCCCUUGAAACUGUUGUUUUCUCUUAGUUCUCAUUAAUUUUUGUGGUCAAUUUCAAAAUAUUUCCACUGUCUAAUUGUAAACAAAAUUUGUUUUAAAUGCUACAGCAAACUCCAAUCUAACAUCCAGGGCCAACAGGGUGAGAGACAAUGGCCGUGUGCCUGGUGACUCCUCCCAAAUUCUUCCUUCCCUGUGCCAAGUUUCAGUGGUGCAUUUGUCAACUUGUGUUGCAGGAACCAACACACACACCACCAGGAAGCCCAACCCUGCAUAUUACUCCCAUUAAUUCAUCCCAGUAAUACUAUUAAACCUUAAUUAAGAGCAUACUAUUUGGAAGUUAAUGAGAUCAUAUAAAUUACUAUAAUGUUAAAAAAUUCACAACAGGUAUACCUGUUCCAGGAGGCUGUGGUAUUUCACAAUACCCCAUGACUUCAAUUUUGCCUUGUUUUGAAAGAUUUUCAUUCAAACAUAAAGUAUGGCCUUAUCUGAGAGUCAGGAAACACUGCAUAUGGGUGCCUUCAUAGAUUUCUAAAAUUAUGAAACUCUCAGACCUUAUUUGAAAAGUUUGUAGGAAAGCAUUAGACUUGGAAUCAGAAGUCUGUGAUCCAGUCUAGGCUUCUGAAAUGGACCAGCUGUGCAAUCUCUAUUUUCAUAUUUUCAUUCAUAUUACAGAAAUUACUAAGCCUUACUGGACAGGUAAUUAUGCAAAUUGAAAAGGGAGCUGAAGGAAUUUGGUGACUGCCAUACAGACAUCAAAUAUUAUUUUUACAUUAAAUGUAAUUAAUUACACCUUAUUUAAAAAUAUAAUUGAAACUAUCUUUUUUGAAAGAAGUAAAUGCAUCCAGGAAAAUUUGCUUCUGUUCUUAUUAAUUUUUUUCUUUAUCAAGUUACCUUAAAUUCUAACUUAGUAUUAACAGAACUUUCUGUUAGUUUGUCUUUAGAGUUAAAUAUUUUUACUAUCAAAGUUACUAUGUGGAUUGUUACAAAGAAUCCGGUAUGAAUUGUUACAAAGAAUCACGUAUUUAGGUAUGGGAGAAGUCUAAAUUUAUGUUUGUGGCUCUGAUCUCUUAUUUACAUUUCUCACAUGGGGAUCGAGAAAUAUUUUAUUUGUGUUAUUAAUACUCAGUUUGUUUCCAAAAGAUAUUGAGAUAAUUAAUUUUAAAAAUCUGUACAAUAAAUCUAUUUAAUUAUGAAGACAAUUUUAAGAGGAAGAGGAACAAAUUUUUGAGCCAUCCAAUGUAAUCUAGUAUCUAUGAUGAAGCAAGAGAAAAAAAAAGUGACUUUUUGUUUUUACUUCCUAAUAAGCCUUCUAGUAGAAUUACAGGUUUACUACUUUUUUCUUUUGACUUCCUCUUUCUAGCAUUUCUUGCACUACAACUUGCUUAAGCUCUUACACUUCAUAGUGAAGCUAUGCACCACCGAGUGAAGCGAUGUGGAACAUUGGAAAGAGUGGGCUUCCUUAGACAGACCUGGGCUUGAAUCCCUGCUCCACUACCUACCAGCUGUGUGACCUUAUACAAGUUACUUAAUGUUUCUGAGCAUCAGGAUAUAAUCUAUAAAAUAGGGAGAAUCACCUCUACCUCAUACAGAUUCUGCAAAGAUUAAACGAGGAGAGGAGGUGAGAGAGUUUUAGGGAUACGUUUUAUUUAAUUUACUAUUUUUGUCUUGAUAAAAUAGUCUGGUUGUAUUCCAAAUGAGACAUUUUAAUACAAAUAAAUUCCAAUCACUUUCUUAAAAAAAAAGAGUUCAUGAAUCAAGGGUUCACGCAAGAAAGAAGCGACCAAUGGUCCUUGUUGGAGAGCAAUGCUGUGUGAGACCACAGGUGUACACAGCCAAGACCAGAGCCAGAGGACAUGCUUCCUCCUGGGUACUUCCAGCCCCUCCCCAGUUCGGGGAAGGCACUGUCAUAAGAAGGUUUCCUGAGGGAUGAUCAGUAUCAGCAUUGUUUGGUAUAUUUACAUAUUUUGAUAAUUAUCGGGUAUGUUGCAAGCUAUGAUGAAAGCAAAACAUACAGCUGGAAAGACGAUCAUUGGUCAGGACCAAAAAACACACACACCUUGGGUGUGAGCAUGCAUUCAGUUGCCUGCAGAGCCUGAGGUCAGGGAAGGUCUCAGAUGGUUCAUACCUUGGUGUAUACAUGAGUUUCAUAGGCCUGGGAUUAAGGAUUAUCCCUGCAAUCUUGCCUGGCAUUGACUUUCUACCUGGUGGGGUGGCAGAAGAAGGGGGUCUUCUAGUCCUCCCAGUAAUGAACACCCCAGUAUAGGAAGUCUUUUUUAGUAAGGCUGUGGUAUGUGUGGUGCAUAUAGGGAAGGGGUUCUGGGAUAGGGGCUGGGUGAAACUCCAAACCUUCAAACAAUGAGUCAAAGUCACUUUAGAAGCAGGAAAGCAGAAAGAAGAUUGACCGUCUUACCAGAUGCAACAAGAUUGAAACAAUGGAGGAUCUUUGUGUGGCAAACACACUCUUUGCCCUCAAUUUAUUCAAGCAUCUGGCAAAAGCAAGCCCCACCCAGAACCUCUUCCUCUCCCCAUGGAGCAUCUCGUCCACCAUGGCCAUGGUCUACAUGGGCUCCAGGGGCAGCACCGAAGACCAGAUGGCCAAGGUGCUUCAGUUUAAUGAAGUGGGAGCCAAUGCAGUUACCCCCAUGACUCCAGAGAACUUUACCAGCUGUGGGUUCAUGCAGCAGAUCCAGAAGGGUAGUUAUCCUGAUGCGAUUUUGCAGGCACAAGCUGCAGAUAAAAUCCAUUCAUCCUUCCGCUCUCUCAGCUCUGCAAUCAAUGCAUCCACAGGGAAUUAUUUACUGGAAAGUGUCAAUAAGCUGUUUGGUGAGAAGUCUGCGAGCUUCCGGGAAGAAUAUAUUCGACUCUGUCAGAAAUAUUACUCCUCAGAACCCCAGGCAGUAGACUUCCUAGAAUGUGCAGAAGAAGCUAGAAAAAAGAUUAAUUCCUGGGUCAAGACUCAAACCAAAGGCAAAAUCCCAAACUUGUUACCUGAAGGUUCUGUAGAUGGGGAUACCAGGAUGGUCCUGGUGAAUGCUGUCUACUUCAAAGGAAAGUGGAAAACUCCAUUUGAGAAGAAACUAAAUGGGCUUUAUCCUUUCCGUGUAAACUCGGCUCAGCGCACACCUGUACAGAUGAUGUACUUGCGUGAAAAGCUAAACAUUGGAUACAUAGAAGACCUAAAGGCUCAGAUUCUAGAACUCCCAUAUGCUGGAGAUGUUAGCAUGUUCUUGUUGCUUCCAGAUGAAAUUGCCGAUGUGUCCACUGGCUUGGAGCUGCUGGAAAGUGAAAUAACCUAUGACAAACUCAACAAGUGGACCAGCAAAGACAAAAUGGCUGAAGAUGAAGUUGAGGUAUACAUACCCCAGUUCAAAUUAGAAGAGCAUUAUGAACUCAGAUCCAUUCUGAGAAGCAUGGGCAUGGAGGACGCCUUCAACAAGGGACGGGCCAAUUUCUCAGGGAUGUCGGAGAGGAAUGACCUGUUUCUUUCUGAAGUGUUCCACCAAGCCAUGGUGGAUGUGAAUGAGGAGGGCACUGAAGCAGCCGCUGGCACAGGAGGUGUUAUGACAGGGAGAACUGGACAUGGAGGCCCACAGUUUGUGGCAGAUCAUCCUUUUCUUUUUCUUAUUAUGCAUAAGAUAACCAACUGCAUUUUAUUUUUCGGCAGAUUUUCCUCACCCUAAAACUAAGCGUGCUGCUUCUGCAAAAGAUUUUUGUAGAUGAGCUGUGUGCCUCAGAAUUGCUAUUUCAAAUUGCCAAAAAUUUAGAGAUGUUUUCUACAUAUUUCUGCUCUUCUGAACAACUUCUGCUACCCACUAAAUAAAAACACAGAAAUAAUUAGACAAUUGUCUAUUAUAACAUGACAACCCUAUUAAUCAUUUGGUCUUCUAAAAUGGGAUCAUGCCCAUUUAGAUUUUCCUUACUAUCAGUUUAUUUUUAUAACAUUAACUUUUACUUUGUUAUUUAUUAUUUUAUAUAAUGGUGAGUUUUUAAAUUAUUGCUCACUGCCUAUUUAAUGUAGCUAAUAAAGUUAUAGAAGCAGAUGAUCUGUUAAUUUCCUAUCUAAUAAAUGCCUUUAAUUGUUCUCAUAAUGAAGAAUAAGUAGGUAUCCCUCCAUGCCCUUCUGUAAUAAAUAUCUGGAAAAAACAUUAAACAAUAGGCAAAUAUAUGUUAUGUGCAUUUCUAGAAAUACAUAACACAUAUAUAUGUCUGUAUCUUAUAUUCAAUUGCAAGUAUAUAAUAAAUAAACCUGCUUCCAAACAACAA